GCUUCCGGCGGCGUCCCGGGGCCAGGGGGGUGCGCCUUUCUCCGCGUCGGGGCGGCCCGGAGCGCGGUGGCGCGGCGCGGGAGGGGUUUUCUGGUGCGUCCUGGUCCACCAUGGCCAAACCAACAAGCAAAGAUUCAGGCUUGAAGGAGAAGUUUAAGAUUCUGUUGGGACUGGGAACACCGAGGCCAAAUCCCAGGUCUGCAGAGGGUAAACAGACGGAGUUUAUCAUCACCGCGGAAAUACUGAGAGAACUGAGCAUGGAAUGUGGCCUCAACAAUCGCAUCCGGAUGAUAGGGCAGAUUUGUGAAGUCGCAAAAACCAAGAAAUUUGAAGAGCACGCAGUGGAAGCACUCUGGAAGGCGGUCGCGGAUCUGUUGCAGCCGGAGCGGCCGCUGGAGGCCCGGCACGCGGUGCUGGCUCUGCUGAAGGCCAUCGUGCAGGGGCAGGGCGAGCGUUUGGGGGUCCUCAGAGCCCUCUUCUUUAAGGUCAUCAAGGAUUACCCUUCCAACGAAGACCUUCACGAAAGGCUGGAGGUUUUCAAGGCCCUCACAGACAAUGGGAGACACAUCACCUACUUGGAGGAAGAGCUGGCUGACUUUGUCCUGCAGUGGAUGGAUGUUGGCUUGUCCUCGGAAUUCCUUCUGGUGCUGGUGAACUUGGUCAAAUUCAAUAGCUGUUACCUCGACGAGUACAUCGCAAGGAUGGUUCAAAUGUUGCAUGAGCUCUGUCUCACUCAUGCUGAACACCCAGCACCGAGAGCAGUGGCUGGCGCACAGCAGGCACCUGAGUGCUUGUUGGGUGGGUGGGACCCCCAGGGAGGAUGAGCCAUGCGUGUUAUUGACGUCAUAGAGUGACUAGACCACAGCCCGUGGUGGCUCGGCCAUCCAGGCAGUGCUGCCGGGACUGAGCUCGGUGCUCCCUGCAGGAUGAUCUGUCUGCUGUGCGUCCGGACCGCGUCCUCUGUGGACAUAGAGGUCUCCCUGCAGGUGCUGGACGCCGUGGUCUGCUACAACUGCCUGCCGGCUGAGAGCCUCCCGCUGUUCAUCGUUACCCUCUGUCGCACCAUCAACGUCAAGGAGCUCUGCGAGCCUUGCUGGAAGCUGAUGCGGAACCUCCUUGGCACCCACCUGGGCCACAGCGCCAUCUACAACAUGUGCCACCUCAUGGAGGACAGAGCCUACAUGGAGGACGCGCCCCUGCUGAGAGGAGCCGUGUUUUUUGUGGGCAUGGCUCUCUGGGGAGCCCACCGGCUCUAUUCUCUCAGGAACUCGCCGACAUCUGUGUUGCCAUCAUUUUACCAGGCCAUGGCAUGUCCGAACGAGGUGGUGUCCUAUGAGAUCGUCCUGUCCAUCACCAGGCUCAUCAAGAAGUAUAGGAAGGAGCUCCAGGUGGUGGCGUGGGACAUUCUGCUGAACAUCAUCGAACGGCUCCUUCAGCAGCUCCAGACCUUGGACAGCCCGGAGCUCAGGACCAUCGUCCAUGACCUGUUGACCACGGUGGAGGAGCUGUGUGACCAGAACGAGUUCCACGGGUCUCAGGAGAGAUACUUUGAACUGGUGGAGAGAUGUGCGGACCAGAGGCCUGAGUCCUCCCUCCUGAACCUGAUCUCCUAUAGAGCGCAGUCCAUCCACCCGGCCAAGGACGGCUGGAUUCAGAACCUGCAGGCGCUGAUGGAGAGAUUCUUCAGGAGCGAGUCCCGAGGCGCCGUGCGCAUCAAGGUGCUGGACGUGCUGUCCUUUGUGCUGCUCAUCAACAGGCAGUUCUAUGAGGAGGAGCUGAUUAACUCAGUGGUCAUCUCGCAGCUCUCCCACAUCCCCGAGGAUAAAGACCACCAGGUCCGAAAGCUGGCCACCCAGUUGCUGGUGGACCUGGCAGAGGGCUGCCACACACACCACUUCAACAGCCUGCUGGACAUCAUCGAGAAGGUGAUGGCCCGCUCCCUCUCCCCACCCCCGGAGCUGGAAGAAAGGGAUGUGGCCGCAUACUCGGCCUCCUUGGAGGAUGUGAAGACAGCCGUCCUGGGGCUUCUGGUCAUCCUUCAGACCAAGCUGUACACCCUGCCUGCAAGCCACGCCACGCGUGUGUAUGAGAUGCUGGUCAGCCACAUUCAGCUCCACUACAAGCACAGCUACACCCUGCCAAUCGCGAGCAGCAUCCGGCUGCAGGCCUUUGACUUCCUGUUGCUGCUGCGGGCCGACUCACUGCACCGCCUGGGCCUGCCCAACAAGGAUGGAGUCGUGCGGUUCAGCCCCUACUGCGUCUGCGACUACAUGGAGCCAGAGAGAGGCUCUGAGAAGAAGACCAGCGGCCCCCUUUCUCCUCCCACAGGGCCUCCUGGCCCGGCGCCUGCAGGCCCCGCCGUGCGGCUGGGGUCCGUGCCCUACUCCCUGCUCUUCCGCGUCCUGCUGCAGUGCUUGAAGCAGGAGUCUGACUGGAAGGUGCUGAAGCUGGUUCUGGGCAGGCUGCCUGAGUCCCUGCGCUAUAAAGUGCUCAUCUUUACUUCCCCUUGCAGUGUGGACCAGCUGUGCUCUGCUCUCUGCUCCAUGCUUUCAGGCCCAAAGACACUGGAGCGGCUCCGAGGCGCCCCAGAAGGCUUCUCCAGAACUGACUUGCACCUGGCCGUGGUUCCAGUGCUGACAGCAUUAAUCUCUUACCAUAACUACCUGGACAAAACCAAACAGCGCGAGAUGGUCUACUGCCUGGAGCAGGGCCUCAUCCACCGCUGUGCCAGCCAGUGCGUCGUGGCCUUGUCCAUCUGCAGCGUGGAGAUGCCUGACAUCAUCAUCAAGGCGCUGCCUGUUCUGGUGGUGAAGCUCACGCACAUCUCAGCCACAGCCAGCAUGGCCGUCCCACUGCUGGAGUUCCUGUCCACUCUGGCCAGGCUGCCGCACCUCUACAGGAACUUUGCCGCGGAGCAGUAUGCCAGUGUGUUCGCCAUCUCCCUGCCGUACACCAACCCCUCCAAGUUUAAUCAGUACAUCGUGUGUCUGGCCCAUCACGUCAUAGCCAUGUGGUUCAUCAGGUGCCGCCUGCCCUUCCGGAAGGAUUUUGUCCCUUUCAUCACUAAGGGCCUGCGGUCCAAUGUCCUCUUGUCUUUUGAUGACACCCCCGAGAAGGACAGCUUCAGGGCCCGGAGUACUAGUCUCAACGAGAGACCCAAGAGUCUGAGGAUAGCCAGACCCCCCAAACAAGGCUUGAAUAACUCUCCACCCGUGAAAGAAUUCAAGGAGAGCUCUGCAGCCGAGGCCUUCCGGUGCCGCAGCAUCAGUGUGUCUGAACAUGUGGUCCGCAGCAGGAUACAGACGUCCCUCACCAGUGCCAGCUUGGGGUCUGCAGAUGAGAACUCCGUGGCCCAGGCUGACGAUAGCCUGAAAAACCUCCACCUGGAGCUCACGGAAACCUGUCUGGACAUGAUGGCUCGAUACGUCUUCUCCAACUUCACGGCUGUCCCGAAGAGGUCUCCUGUGGGCGAGUUCCUCCUAGCGGGUGGCAGGACCAAAACCUGGCUGGUUGGGAACAAGCUUGUCACUGUGACGACAAGCGUGGGAACCGGGACCCGGUCGUUACUAGGCCUGGACUCGGGGGAGCUGCAGUCCGGCCCGGAGUCGAGCUCCAGCCCCGGGGUGCAUGUGAGACAGACCAAGGAGGCGCCGGCCAAGCUGGAGUCCCAGGCUGGGCAGCAGGUGUCCCGUGGGGCCCGGGAUCGGGUCCGUUCCAUGUCGGGGGGCCAUGGUCUUCGAGUUGGCGCCCUGGACGUGCCGGCCUCCCAGUUCCUGGGCAGUGCCACUUCUCCAGGACCACGGACUGCACCAGCCGCGAAACCUGAGAAGGCCUCAGCUGGCACCCGGGUUCCUGUGCAGGAGAAGACGAACCUGGCGGCCUAUGUGCCCCUGCUGACCCAGGGCUGGGCGGAGAUCCUGGUCCGGAGGCCCACAGGGAACACCAGCUGGCUGAUGAGCCUGGAGAACCCGCUCAGCCCUUUCUCCUCGGACAUCAACAACAUGCCCCUGCAGGAGCUGUCUAACGCCCUCAUGGCGGCUGAGCGCUUCAAGGAGCACCGGGACACAGCCCUGUACAAGUCACUGUCGGUGCCGGCAGCCAGCACGGCCAAACCCCCUCCUCUGCCUCGCUCCAACACAGUGGCCUCUUUCUCCUCCCUGUACCAGUCCAGCUGCCAAGGACAGCUGCACAGGAGCGUUUCCUGGGCAGACUCCGCCGUGGUCAUGGAGGAGGGAAGUCCGGGCGAGGUUCCUGUGCUGGUGGAGCCCCCAGGGUUGGAGGACGUUGAGGCAGCGCUAGGCAUGGACAGGCGCACGGAUGCCUACAGCAGGUCGUCCUCAGUCUCCAGCCAGGAGGAGAAGUCGCUCCACGCGGAGGAGCUGGUUGGCAGGGGCAUCCCCAUCGAGCGAGUCGUCUCCUCGGAGGGUGGCCGGCCCUCUGUGGACCUCUCCUUCCAGCCCUCGCAGCCCCUGAGCAAGUCCAGCUCCUCUCCCGAGCUGCAGACUCUGCAGGACAUCCUCGGGGACCCUGGGGACAAGGCCGACGUGGGCCGGCUGAGCCCUGAGGUUAAGGCCCGGUCACAGUCAGGGACCCUGGACGGGGAAAGUGCUGCCUGGUCGGCCUCGGGCGAAGACAGUCGGGGCCAGCCCGAGGGUCCCUUGCCUUCCAGCUCCCCCCGCUCGCCCAGUGGCCUCCGGCCCCGAGGUUACACCAUCUCCGACUCGGCCCCAUCACGCAGGGGCAAGAGAGUAGAGAGGGACGCCUUAAAGAGCAGAGCCACAGCCUCCAAUGCAGAGAAAGUGCCAGGCAUCAACCCCAGUUUCGUGUUCCUGCAGCUCUACCAUUCCCCCUUCUUUGGCGACGAGUCAAACAAGCCAAUCCUGCUGCCCAAUGAGUCACAGUCCUUUGAGCGGUCGGUGCAGCUCCUCGACCAGAUCCCAUCAUACGACACCCACAAGAUCGCCGUCCUGUAUGUUGGAGAAGGCCAGAGCAACAGCGAGCUCGCCAUCCUGUCCAAUGAGCAUGGCUCCUACAGGUACACGGAGUUCCUGACGGGCCUGGGCCGGCUCAUCGAGCUGAAGGACUGCCAGCCGGACAAGGUGUACCUGGGAGGCCUGGACGUGUGUGGUGAGGACGGCCAGUUCACCUACUGCUGGCACGAUGACAUCAUGCAAGCCGUCUUCCACAUCGCCACCCUGAUGCCCACCAAGGACGUGGACAAGCACCGCUGCGACAAGAAGCGCCACCUGGGCAACGACUUUGUGUCCAUUGUCUACAAUGACUCCGGUGAGGACUUCAAGCUUGGCACCAUCAAGGGCCAGUUCAACUUUGUCCACGUGAUCGUCACCCCGCUGGACUACGAGUGCAACCUGGUGUCCCUGCAGUGCAGGAAAGACAUGGAGGGCCUUGUGGACACCAGCGUGGCCAAGAUCGUGUCUGACCGCAACCUGCCCUUCGUGGCCCGCCAGAUGGCCCUGCACGCAAAUAUGGCCUCACAGGUGCAUCAUAGCCGCUCCAACCCCACCGAUAUCUACCCCUCCAAGUGGAUUGCCCGGCUCCGCCACAUCAAGCGGCUCCGCCAGCGGAUCUGCGAGGAAGCCGCCUACUCCAACCCCAGCCUACCUCUGGUGCACCCUCCGUCCCAUAGCAAAGCCCCUGCACAGACUCCAGCCGAGCCCACACCUGGCUAUGAGGUGGGCCAGCGGAAGCGCCUCAUCUCCUCGGUGGAGGACUUCACCGAGUUUGUGUGAGGCCGGGGCCCUCCCUCCUGCACUGGCCUUGGACGGUAUUGCCUGUCAGUGAAAUAAAUAAAGUCCUGACCCCAGUGCACAGACAUAGAGGCACAGAUUGCAGUCAGACAGCUCUUUUAUUGACUUUGUCUGCUUGGUGCGGGGGUUGGGGGGGUGUCGAGGCUCUAGAAGCGGCCAUGCCCACAGAAGUGGUACACAGAAGCAGGCACAGCCAGCUCCGAGGGCCUUGAGGCUGCCUGGGCCAUACAGCACACUCGCGCGUGCGCGCGCGCACACACACACACACACAGUCACCUUCCUCCACCCUGGGAGCCAGCCCCCAGGAGGAGUCUUUUCCUCUAACCACCCUGGGGUCCUCUGACAUGCCUAGUCCUGCUACUUGCCCAGACCUGAUGCCAGCAGGCCUGGGCGCUGCUCUCUUGCUACCUGGCCUGGGGCAAGGGAGGAUGACAAGGCCUCUGGGGUGAUGAGAGUGCCUGGCAGACAGCUGUGCCCCCAGCACCGGCCCAAGGCCAAGCUCGCAUCCAAGCAGCAGCCGGGCUGCCAUAACGCCACCACACCUACCAAGCGCAGCAGGUGUUGGGGGAGGCCAGCUCUGGGCGCAGGCCCCUCAGCCCUAGUGAAAAUAGUGACAUACAAAAAUAUACACAUUUUAACACCAUAUAAAUUACUGACACGAGACACACAGUGAGACGGUGCAGGGAGUACGGUAGGAACUGGAGAGGUAAUAACUUAGGGGCAGGGUGGCGGCGGUGCAGGCUAACCCUCCCUGAAGCCAGCAGCCUUAGCAGUGGGGGACAUCUGCCCAGGGGGUGGGGCCGGGCACAGCCCGCUGUACCUGAGGACUCGGGGAAAUAAAUUAGCAUCUCAGAGGCUAGAAA